ACAUAUCUGCUUCCGACACAGCUGCAAUCACUAGCAAGCUCUCAGGCCUGGCAUCAUGGUGCAUUUUACUGCUGAGGAGAAGGCUGCCGUCACUAGCCUGUGGAGCAAGAUGAAUGUGGAAGAGGCUGGAGGUGAAGCCUUGGGCAGACUCCUCGUUGUUUACCCCUGGACCCAGAGAUUUUUUGACAGCUUUGGAAACCUGUCGUCUCCCUCUGCCAUCCUGGGCAACCCCAAGGUCAAGGCCCAUGGCAAGAAGGUGCUGACUUCCUUUGGAGAUGCUAUUAAAAACAUGGACAACCUCAAGCCCGCCUUUGCUAAGCUGAGUGAGCUGCACUGUGACAAGCUGCAUGUGGAUCCUGAGAACUUCAAGCUCCUGGGUAACGUGAUGGUGAUUAUUCUGGCUACUCACUUUGGCAAGGAGUUCACCCCUGAAGUGCAGGCUGCCUGGCAGAAGCUGGUGUCUGCUGUCGCCAUUGCCCUGGCCCAUAAGUACCACUGAGUUCUCUUCCAGUUUGCAGGUGUUCCUGUGACCCUGACACCCUCCUUCUGCACAUGGGGACUGGGCUUGGCCUUGAGAGAAAGCCUUCUGUUUAAUAAAGUACAUUUUCUUCAGUAAUCAAAAA